GCGCGCGCGCCUGCUCGCCUGCAGCCGGGGAGUCGCGCGGGGCGGGGCCGCGUGCGCGGGGUCGGGGGCGCGCGACCGAAGCGGAUAAGGGACGCGGCGGCGGUUGGCUGUGUCUGUUGAGAGAGUACAGGACAGCCCGGACUGCGAGAGGCGGCGGCGGAGGCAGUAGUUGCACCGGCAGAGGCGGCCGCUGGCAGCGGUUGAGGCGGCGGUCCAACGCGUGCUCUCUGGGCGGGGUGCGGCGGGGGAUGUGCCUGCUCAGGCCGGGCGGAGUCUCUCUGACAGGGCGGGGGAUGCGCCGCGGCCGCUCGCCCGGACCCUGAGGCUGCUGGGCCCACCCUCCCGGAACCGUCCGACCCUCGGUGGCCUCGGCCUCUUCUGCCAUCUCCGGUCCUACCCUGGGGCGGAGGGUGGAAGGCAGCUUCCGUCGAAGAGGAGGGGGCUGCGGUGGCCACCGCGGCGGAGCCCGAGGCAGAAGGAGUCUCUCCCUGUGGCUACCACCUCCCCAGGCCUGUGUUAUUUUACCAAGAAAAUGGUUUGCACGACUUUGAACAUAUACUAUCCAUGCUGAUGGGACAGGAUCCAAUAUGAAUAUAAAUGAUGGAGGAAGACGACGCUUUGAAGAUAAUGAACAUACAUUACGGAUAUAUCCUGGGGCUAUUUCAGAAGGGACAAUCUACUGUCCGAUUCCUGCCAGAAAAAACUCCACAGCUGCUGAGGUGAUUGAGUCUCUUAUAAACAAACUUCAUCUUGACAAAACAAAAUGUUAUGUUCUAGCAGAGGUAAAGGAAUUUGGUGGAGAAGAAUGGAUUCUCAAUCCAACAGAUUGUCCAGUUCAGCGAAUGAUGCUGUGGCCCCGAAUGGCUCUGGAAAAUCGCUUAAGUGGAGAGGACUACCGCUUCCUUCUGAGAGAGAAAAACCUUGAUGGAUCAAUCCAUUAUGGUAGCCUGCAGUCAUGGCUACGGGUAACAGAAGAACGUCGCAGGAUGAUGGAACGGGGUUUUCUUCCACAGCCUCAACAGAAAGACUUUGAUGAUUUAUGUAGUUUACCUGAUUUGAAUGAGAAAACUCUCUUAGAAAACCUACGAAAUCGCUUUAAGCAUGAAAAAAUUUAUACCUAUGUUGGCAGUAUUCUAAUAGUUAUUAACCCAUUCAAGUUUCUUCCUAUUUAUAACCCCAAAUAUGUCAAAAUGUAUGAUAACCACCAACUGGGAAAACUUGAGCCCCACAUUUAUGCUGUGGCUGAUGUAGCUUAUCAUGCCAUGCUUCAGCGCAAAAAGAAUCAGUGCAUCGUGAUUUCAGGAGAGAGUGGUUCUGGGAAGACUCAAAGCACAAACUUUCUUAUUCACCACCUUACUGCUCUCAGUCAGAAAGGAUUUGCCAGUGGAGUAGAACAGAUUAUUCUUGGAGCUGGACCAGUACUUGAGGCCUUUGGAAAUGCAAAGACAGCUCAUAAUAACAAUUCAAGUCGUUUUGGGAAGUUUAUUCAAGUAAAUUACCAGGAAACAGGCACUGUACUUGGUGCCUAUGUUGAAAAAUAUCUACUGGAGAAGUCCAGACUCGUUUAUCAGGAGCAUAAUGAACGGAACUAUCAUGUAUUCUAUUACCUCCUGGCAGGAGCAAGUGAAGAUGAGAGAUCAGCAUUCCAUCUUAAGCAACCAGAGGAAUAUCAUUAUCUCAAUCAGAUAACAAAGAAACCCCUCAGACAGAGCUGGGAUGAUUAUUGCUAUGACUCUGAGCCGGAUUGCUUCACGGUGGAAGGAGAAGAUUUGAGACAUGACUUUGAGCGCCUACAACUUGCCAUGGAAAUGGUAGGAUUUCUUCCCAAGACACGAAGACAGAUUUUCUCUCUUCUCUCAGCCAUACUACAUUUGGGUAAUAUCUGUUACAAAAAGAAGACAUACCGGGAUGACUCCAUUGAUAUCUGUAAUCCUGAAGUUCUGCCUAUUGUCUCAGAAUUAUUAGAGGUUAAAGAAGAGAUGCUAUUUGAAGCAUUAGUUACAAGGAAGACGGUGACAGUGGGAGAAAAGCUUAUUUUGCCAUACAAGUUGGCAGAGGCUGUGACAGUGAGGAACUCCAUGGCUAAGUCUCUGUAUAGUGCCCUGUUUGACUGGAUAGUUUUUCGAAUUAAUCAUGCACUUCUGAAUAGUAAAGAUUUAGAGCAUAAUACCAAGACAUUGUCUAUUGGUGUUCUUGAUAUUUUUGGGUUUGAAGAUUAUGAAAAUAACAGCUUUGAACAGUUCUGUAUUAAUUUUGCUAAUGAACGUUUACAGCACUACUUUAAUCAGCAUAUCUUUAAAUUGGAACAAGAGGAAUAUAGAACUGAAGGUAUCAGCUGGCACAACAUAGAUUACAUUGAUAAUACCUGCUGCAUAAAUCUUAUUAGCAAAAAACCAACAGGACUGCUUCAUCUUUUGGAUGAAGAAAGCAACUUUCCACAGGCUACAAAUCAAACAUUGCUAGACAAGUUUAAGCAUCAACAUGAAGAUAAUUCUUACAUCGAAUUUCCAGCCGUGAUGGAGCCUGCUUUCAUUAUAAAACAUUAUGCUGGAAAAGUAAAAUAUGGGGUAAAGGAUUUCCGGGAAAAAAAUACAGAUCAUAUGCGCCCAGACAUUGUAGCUCUUCUGAGAAGCAGCAAGAAUGCAUUUAUCUCUGGGAUGAUUGGAAUUGAUCCUGUAGCUGUUUUCCGAUGGGCAAUUCUCCGAGCUUUUUUCAGAGCCAUGGUUGCUUUCAGGGAAGCUGGGAAAAGAAACAUUCACAGAAAAACUGGACAUGAUGAUACAGCGCCAUGUGCAAUUUUGAAAAGUAUGGAUAGUUUUAGCUUUCUCCAACACCCAGUCCACCAGAGGAGCUUAGAGAUUCUGCAGAGAUGCAAGGAAGAGAAGUACAGUAUAACCCGGAAAAAUCCCAGAACACCUCUUUCUGAUCUCCAGGGCAUGAAUGCUCUAAAUGAAAAAAACCAACAUGAUACAUUUGAUAUUGCCUGGAAUGGCAGAACUGGGAUUCGCCAGAGCAGACUAUCAAGUGGCACCUCCUUGCUUGAUAAAGAUGGAAUAUUUGCUAAUUCAACUAGCAGCAAACUCCUGGAGAGAGCCCAUGGAAUUCUCACGAGAAACAAAAAUUUCAAAUCCAAGCCUGCCCUUCCAAAGCACUUGCUAGAAGUAAAUUCUUUAAAGCACCUGACAAGACUGACACUACAAGAUCGCAUUACCAAGUCUCUUCUUCAUUUACACAAGAAGAAAAAACCUCCCAGCAUCAGUGCCCAGUUUCAGGCAUCAUUAAGCAAGCUAAUGGAAACACUUGGUCAAGCAGAACCAUAUUUUGUAAAAUGCAUUCGCUCUAAUGCUGAAAAGCUGCCCUUAAGGUUCAGUGAUGUCUUGGUACUUAGACAGCUUCGAUACACCGGGAUGCUGGAAACAGUUCGAAUUCGCCAAUCAGGAUACAGCUCCAAAUAUUCUUUCCAGGAUUUUGUGAGCCACUUCCAUGUACUUCUUCCCCGAAAUAUUAUUCCAUCCAAAUUUAACAUUCAGGAUUUCUUCAGGAAAAUAAAUCUUAAUCCAGAUAAUUAUCAAGUUGGAAAAACCAUGGUCUUUCUAAAGGAGCAGGAACGACAGCACUUACAAGAUCUGCUUCACCAAGAGGUGCUCCGCAGAAUCAUAUUGUUGCAGCGAUGGUUCAGGGUCUUGCUGUGUAGGCAGCAUUUCCUCCAUCUGAGACAAGCAUCUGUUAUUAUCCAGAGAUUCUGGAGGAAUUACCUAAAUCAGAAGCAAGUCAGAGAUGCAGCUGUGCAGAAGGAUGCUUUUGUUAUGGCUAGUGCAGCUGCUCUUCUCCAAGCUUCCUGGCGUGCUCACUUAGAGAGGCAGCGGUACUUGGAGUUACGGGCUGCAGCCAUCGUUAUCCAGCAGAAAUGGAGAGAUUACUAUAGGCGCAGGCACAUGGCUGCUAUUUGCAUACAAGCAAGAUGGAAAGCCUACAGGGAAAGUAAAAGGUACCAAGAACAAAGGAAAAAAAUUAUCCUUUUGCAAUCAACAUGUAGAGGAUUCAGAGCAAGACAAAGAUUUAAAGCUUUAAAAGAACAAAGGCUAAGAGAAACAAAGCCAGAAGUUGGAUUGGUGAAUAUUAAGGGAUAUGGAUCUCUGGAAAUUCAGGGUUCAGACCCUUCAGGAUGGGAGGAUUGUUCUUUUGACAACAGAAUAAAAGCCAUAGAGGAAUGUAAAUCUGUAAUAGAGAGUAAUCGAAUUAGCCGUGAAAGUUCAGUGGACUGCUUGAAGGAGUCACCAAACAAGCAGCAGGAGAGAGCCCAAAGCCAGAGUGGUGUGGACUUGCAGGAAGAUGUGCUUGUAAGAGAGAGACCCAGAUCCUUGGAGGAUCUCCAUCAGAAAAAAGUAGGCCGGGCUAAGAGAGAAAGUAGGAGAAUGAGAGAACUAGAGCAAGCUAUAUUUAGCUUAGAAUUGCUGAAAGUUCGUUCUCUUGGUGGUAUUUCUCCUUCAGAGGAUCGCAGAUGGUCUACAGAAUUGGUGCCUGAAGGCCUUCAGUCUCCACGGGGUACACCUGAUAGUGAGAGCUCUCAAGGAAGCUUGGAACUUCUGAGCUAUGAGGAAAGCCAAAAGAGCAAACUAGAGUCUGUCAUUUCAGAUGAAGGAGACUUGCAGUUUCCAUCACCUAAGAUAUCCAGCAGUCCAAAAUUUGAUUCACGGGACAAUGCCCUCAGUGCCUCAAAUGAGACUAGCAGUGCAGAGCAUUUGAAGGAUGGAACUAUGAAGGAAAUGGUGGUCUGCAGUUCUGAGUCUAUUACCUGUAAACCACAGCUGAAAGACUCCUUCAUUUCAAAUAGUCUACCUACUUUUUUUUAUAUCCCCCAACAAGACCCACUGAAAACAAAUUCCCAACUAGACACAAGUAUCCAAAGAAACAAACUAUUGGAAAAUGAAGACACAGCGGGGGAAGCUCUUACUUUGGAUAUCAACAGGGAAACUAGAAGGUAUCACUGCUCAGGAAAAGAUCAGAUUGUUCCUUCUUUGAAUACAGAGUCUUCUAAUCCUGUGCUUAAGAAGUUAGAAAAGCUAAACACUGAGAAGGAAGAAAGGCAAAAACAGUUGCAGCAACAGAAUGAAAAAGAGAUGAUGGAACAGAUUCGCCAGCAAACAGAUAUUUUAGAGAAGGAGCGCAAAGCCUUCAAGACAAUUGAAAAGCCAAGAAUUGGAGAGUGUUUGGUGGCACCAUCUUCCUAUCAGUCAAAGCAAAGAGUAGAGAGGCCAUCCUCUCUCCUCAGCUUAAAUACCUCAAAUAAGGGAGAACUUAAUGUACUGGGGUCCCUAUCAUUAAAAGAUGCAGCUCUUGCCCAAAAAGACAGUUCCUCUGCUCACUUACCCCCAAAGGACCGACCUGUCACCGUGUUCUUUGAAAGAAAAGGAAGUCCAUGCCAAUCUAGUACUGUCAAGGAAUUAUCCAAGACAGACAGAAUGGGCACCCAGCUGAAUGUAGCCUGUAAACUCUCAAAUAAUCGCAUUUCAAAAAGAGAACACUUUAGGCCAACUCAGUCUUACAGCCACAAUUCUGAUGACCUUUCCAGAGAGGGAAAUGCUAGGCCCAUUUUCUUCACUCCAAAGGACAAUAUGAGUAUUCCCCUUGUCAGCAAAGAAGCCUUAAACAGUAAAAAUCCUCAACUCCAUAAAGAAGAUGAACCAGCAUGGAAACCUGUGAAGUUAGCUGGGCCAGGCCAAAGAGAGCAGGUUGCCAGACCGGCCCAUAAAAAGAAAGCUCGAAUGGCGCGGACGCGCUCCGAUUUCUUGACUAGAGGUACUUUUGCCGAUGGGGAGGGGGAUACAGAGGAAGAUGAUUACGAUGACAUUAUUGAGCCCCUUCUCUCCCUUGACCAAGCUUCUCACUGUGAGCUAGGGCCUGCACCCAGCCUGGGUCAGGCCUCUCACAGUGACUCCGAAAUGACAUCACAGCGAUUUUCGUCAGUUGAUGAACAAGCAAAACUUCAUAAGACUAUGUCUCAAGGAGAGAUUACCAAGUUGGCAGUGAGACAGAAGGCUUCAGAUUCAGAUAUAAGACCUCAGAGAGCUAAGAUGAGAUUCUGGGCCAAAGGGAAACAAGGGGAGAAGAAGACUACCAGAGUGAAACCUACUACCCAGUCAGAGGUUUCGCCACUCUUUGCAGGCACAGAUGUGAUUCCAGCUCAUCAGUUUCCAGAUGAAUUAGCUGCAUAUCACCCAACACCUCCUUUGAGCCCAGAACUGCCCGGCAGUUGCCGGAAGGAAUUCAAAGAGAACAAAGAACCUUCUCCAAAGGCUAAGCGCAAGCGAAGUGUGAAGAUUAGCAACGUGGCUUUGGAUUCUAUGCAUUGGCAAAAUGACUCUGUCCAGAUCAUAGCAAGUGUCAGUGAUUUAAAAAGCAUGGAUGAAUUUCUUCUGAAAAAGGUGAAUGACCUAGAUAAUGAAGACAGCAAGAAGGAUACACUAGUGGAUGUUGUAUUUAAAAAAGCCCUGAAGGAAUUUCGGCAGAAUAUCUUCAGCUUUUAUUCAUCUGCAUUGGCGAUGGAUGAUGGGAAAAGCAUACGGUAUAAAGACCUCUAUGCACUAUUUGAACAGAUUCUGGAAAAGACGAUGAGGCUUGAGCAGCGUGAUUCACUGGGUGAAUCUCCAGUGAGAGUUUGGGUCAACACUUUUAAAGUGUUUUUAGAUGAAUAUAUGAAUGAAUUCAAGACUUCAGAUUGCACAGCCACAAAGGUGCCAAAAACAGAAAGAAAGAAAAGAAGGAAAAAGGAAACUGAUUUGGUGGAAGAACACAAUGGUCACAUCUUUAAAGCCACCCAAUAUAGCAUCCCUACAUACUGUGAAUACUGUUCUUCUUUGAUAUGGAUAAUGGACCGAGCCUCUGUUUGCAAAUUAUGCAAGUAUGCUUGCCAUAAGAAGUGCUGUCUGAAAACCACAGCCAAGUGCUCUAAAAAGUAUGAUCCAGAGCUGUCAUCUCGACAAUUUGGGGUUGAACUGUCCCGUUUGACCAGUGAAGACCGAACUGUUCCUUUAGUAGUGGAAAAGCUCAUAAACUACAUUGAAAUGCAUGGACUGUAUACAGAAGGUAUUUAUCGAAAGUCUGGUUCGACUAAUAAAAUCAAGGAGCUUCGGCAGGGUCUAGAUACAGAUGCUGAGAGUGUAAAUCUAGAUGACUAUAACAUACACGUCAUUGCAAGUGUAUUCAAACAAUGGCUUCGAGAUUUGCCCAAUCCUCUCAUGACCUUUGAACUCUAUGAGGAAUUUCUUCGAGCUAUGGGCCUUCAGGAGAGGAAGGAGACAAUCCGUGGUGUAUACUCUGUGAUUGAUCAACUCUCCCGAACUCAUCUCAAUACACUGGAACGCCUCAUCUUUCAUCUAGUCAGGAUUGCUCUGCAGGAAGACACUAAUCGAAUGUCUGCUAAUGCUUUGGCCAUUGUGUUUGCGCCCUGCAUUCUCCGCUGCCCUGACACCACUGACCCACUACAAAGUGUACAGGACAUCAGUAAGACUACCACUUGUGUGGAACUGAUUGUUGUGGAACAAAUGAAUAAAUACAAGGCUCGUCUCAAAGAUAUCAGUAGCUUGGAAUUUGCUGAGAAUAAGGCAAAGACCAGGUUGUCACUGAUUCGUAGAUCAAUGAAACCUGUACUAAUUGCAGUUAGAUUCAUGAACAUUACCCGCAAUUCAGUCUCGGGAAAGGGGCGUAUUCGUCGAGGAAACUAUCCAGGUCCAUCGUCUCCUGUUGUAGUUCGGUUGCCUUCUGUGUCUGAUGUCUCAGAGGAGACCUUGACUAGUGAGGCAGCCAUGGAGACUGACAUCACAGAACAGCAGCAAGCAGCUAUGCAGCAGGAGGAGAGAGUACUGACUGAGCAGAUUGAGAACCUACAGAAGGAGAAGGAGGAGCUAACAUUUGAGAUGCUUGUACUGGAACCCCGUGCCUCUGAUGAUGAAACCCUUGAGUCUGAGGCCUCCAUUGGGACUGCUGAUAGCUCAGAGAAUUUGAAUAUGGAGUCUGAAUAUGCUAUCUCUGAGAAAUCAGAAAGAAGCUUAGCCCUUAGCUCCCUGAAGACAGCUGGCAAGUCUGAACCUUCCAGCAAGUUGCGAAAGCAACUUAAAAAGCAGCAAGACUCUUUAGAUGUCGUGGACUCUUCGGUCUCCUCUUUAUGUCUGUCUAACACGGCAUCAUCUCAUGGGACCAGAAAACUAUUUCAGAUUUAUUCCAAAUCUCCAUUCUACCGAGCUGCCUCAGGUAAUGAGGCCCUGGGAAUGGAAGGACCAUUGGGCCAGACCAAAUUCCUGGAAGACAAGCCUCAGUUCAUCAGCAGAGGAACCUUCAACCCGGAAAAGGGCAAACAAAAAUUAAAGAAUGUGAAAAACUCACCUCAGAAAACCAAAGAGACCCCAGAGGGGACAGUCAUGUCUGGCCGCAGAAAAACUGUGGACCCAGACUGCACCUCCAACCAACAGCUAGCACUCUUUGGAAAUAAUGAAUUUAUGGUCUGAACCGGCAGAUGUGUGUCCCUCCGUGGCUACAGAGUGGUAAACAAAUCUCACCUUUGGGGCUGCGUUUCAUCACCUCGUCCACAAUAGUCAAUCCUAAUUGUGGUCCUGCCUCUUUUCUAAGCAUAUGGCUAAGACUGUAUGUGCUGAAUUCCUGGGCCUCCUGCAGAAGCAGAAAGCCUGCUGGGGAUGGUGCCAGCUGUGCCUUGGCUGUUGUAUUUGAAUUGAGAUUUUUACUAUACAAAGCCACCUAGGGCCUGGGGAUUUGGGUCAGUUGUAGUUGCCUCUCCCCCACCCUCUUUUCCCUUCCCAAAGGUGGGUGUUGAACUAGGGGGGAUAUUGCUGUCCUGAGGGACCCUCUCAUUUCUGACAUUUGAAGAAAACGUAUAAAUCUUUCUUAACCGUGAAAGCAAAAGCCUUUGGGUUUAUUUUGGGAUAGUUAGGAGCUAGGGUAGAAUAUAAUUUUUUUCCAAAAACUUACUUACAAACAAAAAGCCUAAUCCCUCUAUUUUAAGAUUUCUGAAAAAACACUCCAUGUUAUAUUCUGGGGAAAGCAAAAACAAAAAAAAAAAACAAAAAAAAAAAAACAAAAAAAAACCGUGAUUGUUUCCAUUAAGCCAUCAGAGCGUGUCUCAGAUAUCUUGUUAUACAGUGAAGAAGAGAAUACCUAUUUUUUUUGAUGAUGUUUGAUGUCAUAGUAAUCAGUGCUGGUUUAACUCCUGUUUAGUUCCUGCCAAAUACAUUGCAUGGGCUGAAGUGUCAGUAGCCAUACUGUUCUCAUGUUUCUUGGUCCUAGGAUCAGAUUCUUCUACAUUAUUUUUUAGUUUCCCAGAGACAUGGUGAUCCCUAAACUUAUGAAGGUUUCAUCCUAAGCCAUUCAGGCUUUUCUCUUUGUAUAGAUUAAACCGAAAACCGCAUAUGAGCCUGUUCAUCUGCUGGUGGAUUCCCACCACAGACUCAGACUCAAACAAACAAACAAAUAAUGUGACCGUUUAGUUAGUUUCCAAAAACAUUCACAUACAAUAUUGCAUGAAUAAGUAAGUAAGUGUUACAGAAAGCUGCCAAAAAAUAAAAAGGUUUUUAAUAUGACCUAUCUAACUAACUAACUUUUAUCUUCCUUUUCUCAGACUAUCAGUAUUAAAUAGAUGGAAAAAAAUCAAGGACUACUUGAAGCUAUUUUUGUUAAUAUUCUGGUUACUGAAGUUUAUUGUAAAUAUGUAUGUAUAGUAGGCAUAUUUCUUUUUAACCUUGUGCUUCCCUCCUUCCCAUGGAAUUUCUUCCCACAGAUGAGGGGCCACUGGACAGGGGGAUGAGAGCCAUUCGUCCCUGGGUUGAGGGAAUUAGUAAGACAUCAUUUUCACCACUGGGUGGUCUUCAUACACAUGAGUUAUAAUAGCAUUUUAAGUAUCUUAGCAUUUGUGGGAUUAGAAAUCUGUUUUUGCUAUUUAUAAUAUAUAAAAAAUGAAACAUGAUAGCCUUUCUUGAGAUAAGUAUGUGAAAUGUUUAUUUUUAAAGUUACUAAAUGCAUCUUGUCUUGCUACUACAUGCACUGCUCUGAAAAAGAGCCUUUACCAUCUAUAACCUGUAUUUUGGGUAUUCUUCCUUUUCAUACUUCUUUGAAGUUGUGGAAAUAUUAAGUCUUUUGUUAAGGCAGAGUCUCUCUCUCCUGUUACACAACACUGAACCUCACGCCACUGCCUCAGUGGUUAUUGGCCAGCCCCAGAGGUUAGACUUGGAGCAUAAUUCUGAGUGGCAGCUAAAGGUAGCAGGAGUCUUACCUCUCCCUACUUUGGGUUCAGAAUUGAGCCAGAGAAAGGAAGCCAUUAAAAUCUCCAGAAUAAUGAUAGUUAAUGAGCAAAUGUUAUGCUUUAUAUCCCACAGACAUCUGCCACCUUGUUCAUCUUGUCCUGAGGAGUAAUAAAUAAUGUUAAGCUUUUAAAAAUCUGAAUUUCAGAGAAUCUCCUAGAGGAUAGAGGAAAACCCCUCAGCAUGGUGUGUUAGAGUGGGAUUGCUGGUUCCUCAGCCCCGUGCCAGGUUGCACAGUCUGUGUUUCAGUGUUCUUGGGAGAGUAGUGUACUGCUGGGCAUUAAUUGUUACUCUGCACUUGCUCCAGAAUGUUGGUUAAAUCCUGUAUGAAAAAAAGAGAUUGCCCUUAUGGAAUAAUUUCCUGUGGCCCAGAGGAAUGGCCAGAAGAACAUAUGUUGGCACAUGUUCUUCCUUCUAAAUCUUUGUGGGGCUUUUUUGGCAAAAUAAGUUUUUUGGCAGUUAAAAAACGACUGAUGUAGGUCACUUUAAAGGAACUAGGUGAUGGAUGUUAAGAGACUUUAUAAUUUUUCUCAGGGACCUGAAACUCCAGUUUGGAUAAAAUUCAAUUAAAAAAACUUGUUUUUUCAGUUGCUAGAUUUGUGGAUUUCUAGUAAUUUAAUCUGCCAGGAUUGGGGUGGGUGGGUGAGGAGGAGAGAGCCACAAAAUGAUAAGAGUGGAGAGCAGUGUGGGGCCCUCCCUUUGAGGGAAAGCCGUUGUUUACAUAGGGUAGUAGGCCUUGUUGGCCUGAUCAAGAGAUGAAGCCAUAACUCUUAAAAACCUUCAGAACCAAACGCUGUGUCUGCAUCCAUCUGUUCUCACUGGCCCUCUGCAUGGUAAAGUUAUGUCACCACAAAGUGAUGCCGCAUUACAAUCACUUAUGAAACUGUUAGCCCUUAAUAUGCAUCACAUUUGUGGUUCCAUAGUGCUUCUCCUUUGCUUGUUUGAUCUCUGCAUGGCAGCAGUGGGGCAGCUCCACAUUUGGAGCCCAUACUCCAAAAUGCAGAGCACUCUUCUCACAGCACACAUUCCCAGCCCCAAACAAAACCUGAAUUUUCAACUCUGCCCAUUAAAGUGAAUGUAUCCCUGUAAUUUAGUAUGUACUUAUUAUGGAAAAUGUAACAAAAGCAGAGAAGUGUGAUUUCAUUCUGUAUCACAAAUUGAAGCAAAUCAACAGCAAAUACAGCAGGAUUCAGGGAGGCUUAGUUUACAACGUACUUUGUACCUCCUGCCAUUUAAAUUAUUUUGCCACUCUGGGCUUCUGAAAACACAAAGGGAGAUACAGCCCUCCAACUAUGAGCCUUGCAGAGAGAGACAAAAGGGCCAGAGGUCCUGGGAUGGAAUACUAGAGCCCCCACCUUCUCAUGCUUUGGAAACCUGCCAGAGCACUUACCCUGCUGGAAGAUUAAUGAAGACUCCAUUCUGUGUUUCAUAACAGUAGCGUUGUUUUCUCCAUCAAAAACAGAGGGUCACAGAAAUGUGCUGAAAAGAUGUGGUCCAGCAAGGUUCUGUAGUCCCACCUCAGUGCCUGUGGGCUGUGUUUUUCACUGUAACAAGCACUUUGGUAAACUAGAAAGAAGAAAGGAUUCUCAGGAUGUGUUCAAAGCUAAGAGAGUUUUCAUUUUAAAAAGAAACAUACAUACUCACUCCAUGGCUUUCCUCAUCCUCCUCUCUUUUUUCUUCUUGGUGGGAAGCUGGAUGCGGGGCAUGCAUCAUUCUGUAUGGACAAAUGUGUUAUGUCCACCCAUACUCUUGUGACAACUCCCCAGCACUGUCCUGCAAUACCAUGCUGGCCUUGGUAGUAAAACUCCUUGGUAUCUGUGAGAGUCCUCUUUUUCUAUGCCCUAGACUACUUUUAACCACUUUUCUCUGGAAUGACUCCCACAUUUGAUUGGGUAUUGAAAGGGUAACAGCAAAAUGAUGAUUGUGGAGAUGGAUCUAUUAGGUCUCAUGUUGGUCCCCUGGUUGAAACUAUUUUCAAAAAAGCCCCAACAAUGGGCCUGUCACCUUGCUAGUCAUCCAUUCUUAAUGCCUAUUUAUCAGCCCUCUGAGGUCAUAUAAAAGUUGCACCUUUUGAACCAAGUAUUUGUAUUUACUAUGGGAAAGGUGUGGACUACAGAUUCGUAUUAUAUUAUUUUAAUGGAUUUUAAGUAAUUUAUAAGUAUGCUGAGUGUAAAUUUUUUUUAAAAACUGUAUUAUAAAAGGACAUAUCCUGUGAAAUAUAACAUUUUACUGUUUAAUAGAAUAAUUCUAUAAGAAGAAUGAUUUAUCUCACCCACGGAACUGAUUACAUUCCGGAUGCAAUCAAUAGGCACUUUGUAAUUUCCUUUUUGUUUUUUUUUCUUUGCUGGGGGGUUGAGGGGUAACAAGAUACCAUCUGUAUAAAGUGCAGUUUGUGUCACUCAAAAUAUGCACUGUAUGGCUACACAAAAGCAGCUUGAUGAACAAAUCACCCCAUGGCUCAUUAAAGAACAAAGCUUCCAGAAGCA